AGUCAACGCAGAAGGAGCGAGAACGUUCGGCCGAAAAGCCCGGCACAGAGAAGGGAGGGGUGCUGAAAGCCGCGGACUGCAGCCGCUGGCCUGGCUGCCGCCCCGAAACAACGCCCACGCCCGGGAGAAGGGCAGGCUGGCGUCCAGGUAGGACUCCCUCAGGCCGCCCCGCCAGGGGCCGCGCCGAGCGGAGCGGCUGGACCCCAACCCUGCCGGCCGCCGCCGAGGUGCGCAGCCCGCAGCCCCACACCCACGGCCUUUGCAACACCCCAACCGUUGAACUGCGCCCCUACACGCCCGGCGUCUGCGGCUCCCAGGCCGGUGCCGAUGACGUCAGACUUACGUCAGGCGUGACGCCACGGCUGGGAGGAGUGAGGACGGCGCGGGAGGGCGUUUCCGGAGCACGCGCCGGGCGGGGGCCGCUGACGUCGGGCUCAGGGCCGCGGCCAGAGGGCUAGAAUCCGCGCCUUCCGAGGGAGCCGCGCCCUGCGGGCCCCACCGUACCCGAGGGGAUGGAGGGCUGCCCCCGAGGCCCCCGCGCGGCUCGCGGUCCCACGCCUGCCGGCCCGCGCUAGCUACUCGACUCGUGCGCUAAAUUUAUCCGUCACCCAGGCCUUGUCUCCCGAGUCAUUGGCGUCGUGGUUCAAAAGAAAUGGAAGAAAAGGAGCGAUGUGACCGAUUGUGUUCGGUCCUCCUGCUUUGAGGCCUGGCAUUUGCAGAGGGAAACAGCAAGAAAAUCGUGGGGAUUUUGGAGGGGGGUGGGAGGGAAGGGUGGGGAAACGGAAACAAGGUCUUACAUUUUAUGUGUUUUUUUAAAUUCUGCACUUUGACAGUGGUAGCAAAAUAAAAGUAAUCCAAAAGUUAUUUUUCUAUUGAGAAGAGAGAAGAGGUGGGUUUUAUUUUUUUCCUUUUGAUUCCAAUCUUUUCUCCCAGUGACAAAGCAUAAAUCAUGGACACCAGAGAAUAAGGUGGACCUCAGGAAUCCGGAAAAGACUGAGAAGCUUACAUUCUUCCUCUAGAGGGAAGAGUGGGGUGUUUAUAGCCAUCUCUGGAACCUAAAACAAAAAACAUGAGUUGUGUGCCAUGGAAAGGAGACAAGGCCAAAUCUGAAUCAUUGGAGCUGCCCCAGGCAGCACCCCCACAAAUCUACCAUGAGAAACAGCGCAGGGAGCUUUGUGCCCUCCACGCCCUCAAUAACGUCUUCCAGGACAGCAAUGCCUUCACCCGGGAUACGCUGCAAGAGAUUUUCCAGAGGUUGUCUCCAAACACCAUGGUGACACCUCACAAGAAGAGCAUGCUGGGAAAUGGCAACUACGAUGUGAAUGUCAUUAUGGCAGCACUUCAGACCAAAGGCUAUGAAGCUGUUUGGUGGGACAAGCGCAGGGAUGUCGGUGUCAUUGCCCUCACUAACGUCAUGGGCUUCAUCAUGAAUCUGCCCUCCAGCCUAUGCUGGGGUCCACUGAAACUGCCCCUCAAAAGGCAGCACUGGAUCUGUGUUCGAGAGGUGGGAGGGGCCUACUACAACCUCGACUCCAAACUCAAGAUGCCCGAGUGGAUUGGAGGCGAGAGCGAGCUCAGGAAGUUUCUAAAACAUCAUUUGCGAGGAAAGAACUGUGAACUCCUGCUGGUGGUACCAGAAGAGGUAGAGGCUCAUCAGAGUUGGAGGACCGAUGUGUAACAGUUCUGCCCAACCUCCCUCUCGCCUCAGCCCCUUCAGUCCUCUGUGACGUGCUGUGGCCUCUACAGUGGGUCUGCCCUUGCCACUUCCCCAAACAUCUCAUCAAGUUUUUCCCCUUCAGAUCUGACAGUGCAAUAGGACAGACGUGUGGACUGUUAUAAGAACUACUCAGUGUUUUGUUCCUGGGCAAGGAAGGUAGGAGUUCUGUGCACUUAAGGCCAGUGGUCACAAACCCUUGUUUUAUUUAAGAGACAGAGGAGAAAGUGGAGCGGGGAGGGAAUCCUAGCUUAUUUUCCCUUUUCUAUGAGGACUUGACACAGGUUCUGCUGAGUUGUCACUGCUGCUCCAGACUCACCUAGAGAUGCUGCCUCCACUUUCCAUCCUGUCUGGGUCUGAAAACAGUGGGUCUGCAGAUAGUGCCCACAAACCCCAUGUGACUGGUUUGAAGGACCCAGAGCAUAAAGGUCUCUCAGGAAACCAUGUCCAAAACCCUAGCAGCGGUACAGCAUGCUGUCUCCAACCCUUAUCCCCAGGUUUAAGGGUGGUUUAUGGCCAUACGUGGAGGUUUUUUGUUGUUGUUUUUGAGACUGAGUUUCACUCUUGUUGCCCAGGCUGGAGUGCAAUGGCACCAUCUCGGCUCACUGCAACCUCCACCUCCUGGUUCAAGCGAUUCUCAGGCCUCAGCUUCCCAAGUAGUUGGGAUUACAGGCGCCUGCCACCACACCUGGCUAAUUUUGUAUUUUUAGUAGAGAUGGGGUUUCUCCAUGUUGGUCAGGCUGGUCUCAAACUCCCGACCUCAAGUGAUCUGCCCGCCUUGGCCUCCCAAAGUGCUGGGAUUACAGGCGUGAGCCACCGCACCCGGCAGAGUUUUAUAAUGAAAAAUUAACUAAUAUUCUAGUAUGAAGUGAGGAGGAUACUGAACAGGAUGUGGCUAAAGCCAACCUGGGACAGCCAUGGGGUGGCUUGGUUUCUUCACUCCAGUGUUGUCCCUACCAUUUCGCAGCAUUGAUUUAGGAGGCUCUGGGACAAAAGAGAAGCCAAAGAGCAGUUUUCCCAGUUCACUCACUCUGGCAAAAUCAGGAAAAAAAAGUCUGCUUUUGACAUCAAAUUCCACUAAUUUGGGGCAGCGUUGGGUGAGGAAAGUAUUGUGAAGACAGGCUUCUUGGAGUAGGGGCAGCCACAAUUCAGUAGACACUCUAGGCUCGGAGGCUGCCACUGUAGUUGCCAAGCUCAGGUUGGGUGGUUCUGUGCUGUAUGGAUGGAAUAGGACCUGGGCUGGUCAUCUUCAUGUCGUUUCCUCUCUGUAUCAAUGGAAGUUCAACCCGCCCCUACCUCUUCAGAUAGUUGUAGGCCACUUUUCUCUUGUAACUUUGGAAAACAAAAGAGGAGAAAUAAGUAUCAUACCAUAUGCGUGUCUCCAAAGUGGAUGUGGUUGCCUCAAGGCAGGUGGCAGGCAGGGGUGACCUGCUGGCCCUCAGAUCAAUGGUCGUGGCAGGUCUGAGAGCUGUCCCACUGGCCAGACUUCUCUCCAGCAGCAAAGCCAGCCUGGGGCUUGCAUGUUGAUCCUGAGCAAGCUUAACGGGGUGAAGCUGGGCUUUCUCCCCCCUGUGACUGGAGUGCAUGUUGACACCAGCACUUUUUCUGCACAUGUAUCUUCAAUCCAACAAGGCCGUUUUUUUAAUGCUGAGUAACAGGCCACCAAGCGGCUACUGCGUUAUAUCUUCUCAGCAACUGGCCGCAGUCUCUUCUGCACCAUUUUCUACACCAGACCUGCUUGGCACCACAGGGAGCUCUUUUCCUGCCCUGCACAAUGACAUUCCAACCACCACCAGCCAGACAUUACAGCCAACCUUGCUGAUUGUCACAAGCAGGACCUUGGGGCCACUGGCACUGUCAGAUAGUAAGCCAUUUCUUGGGUAGAGGAGGAAACUCCUCUCCACAAAUCCACUUGGGCCUGUGCAAAUGGCACUUGAAAGAGUCCCCAUGCACUUGGAGUCCAUGAGCCAAUGGGAUAUGCAAAGACGCUUAAACAUUUCAGGGCUGGUUUCUCUGUUCAUAUCCAAUUCUGGUGCUUAGGAACAGGGACCCAUGCUGAUGCCCAAGGGCAAAAAGCCCCACUUCCUUUAAGGAAGUGAACAGGCCUGACCCUGAUGCCCAAUAACGGGCAACCCUAGGCUUUUUGUUUUUCUUGCUUUUAUUCCUUUUUGUUGUUGGCCUUGUGCUGCGUUUGUUUACAAAAGAUGUAUUUUGUUUAACCAAAUAUUAAAAAUGGAAAACUCCAUAUAUGUCUCCUUGUCUGCCUGAAUUCUAUAAUUGUGUAAAGAAAAAUAAACUUUAGUAUGACGCUGUUUUAAAAGGA